AGAGUCCUGGCGAGGGCGCUGGCCGAGAGGUGCUCGGCUUGUAGCAGGUCCCGCACUCCAGCCUCUCGCUGCCAGGGUUUGCUCUCUGCUUGUCCUGGGCUGAGGUGUCCAUGACGGAGUCAUCCAAGGAGGAAAAAAUCUGUUCCGGGUGAGCCCAGGCCGCCCCGGAUAUGCGAUGGCUGAGGAGCAGACACCAGGGACCACACUGAGGUUGGGUUUCAGACCAAGACACUGGAUUCUCCUAGUUAAGAUAAAGAGCUUUGGGUGCCUGACAGUGAAAAUGGUGUAAUCUGCGUUAACAGUUCACAGCUUGAAGGCAUGACAAUUAAAGAACACACAUGGACUUGUGGCACAUGGAAAUGUGCGCACAGAAAAAGGAAAUCUAUAAUUCUUUUAAAGUAGGAAGGCAUUCUUCCUUGCCAAAAUGGGUACAUUCUGUUCGGUUAUCAAGUUUGAAAAUCUACAAGAAUUAAAGAGACUGUGUCACUGGGGUCCCAUCAUAGCCCUUGGUGUUAUAGCAAUAUGUUCUACCAUGGCCAUGAUUGACUCUGUGUUGUGGUAUUGGCCCUUACAUACAACUGGAGGAAGUGUGAAUUUCAUCAUGUUGAUAAAUUGGACUGUCAUGAUUCUUUAUAAUUACUUCAAUGCCAUGUUUGUCGGUCCGGGCUUUGUCCCUCUGGGGUGGAAACCGGAAAUUUCUCAGGAUACCAUGUAUCUCCAGUAUUGUAAAGUCUGCCAAGCAUACAAGGCACCACGUUCACAUCACUGCAGAAAGUGUAACAGAUGUGUGAUGAAGAUGGACCAUCACUGUCCUUGGAUCAACAACUGUUGUGGUUACCAAAAUCAUGCUUCGUUCACACUGUUUCUCCUUUUAGCACCACUGGGUUGUAUCCAUGCUGCUUUCAUUUUUGUGAUGACUAUGUACACACAGCUUUAUCAUCGGAUGAAAAUAAUUCUCAGAAACAAAACUUCUAUUGAGUCAUGGAUUGAAGAGAAGGCUAAAGAUCGAAUUCAGUAUUAUCAACUAGAUGAAGUCUUUGUUUUUCCAUAUGAUAUGGGAAGUAGAUGGAGGAACUUUAAACAGGUAUUUACGUGGUCAGGGGUCCCUGAAGGAGAUGGACUUGAGUGGCCAGUAAGAGAAGGCUGUCACCAAUACAGCUUAACAAUAGAACAGUUGAAACAAAAAGCAGAUAAGAGAGUCAGAAGUGUUCGCUAUAAAGUAAUAGAAGAUUAUAGUGGUGCCUGCUGCCCUCUGAAUAAAGGAAUCAAAACCUUCUUCACAAGUCCCUGCACCGAAGAGCCUCGAAUACAGCUGCAAAAAGGGGAAUUCAUUUUAGCCACAAGAGGUUUACGAUACUGGUUAUAUGGAGACAAAAUUCUUGAUGAUUCCUUUAUAGAAGGGGUCCUUGUUUAAGACUGAUUUUCAUCAUGGUCCAUGAGGAAAGAAACACCACAACGUAAGUAUCUGUAAUAGUUUAUUUUAAAGACUUUACAUUUACAAGUAGAAACAACAUGUGUUAUCUGUGGGUAAGGUAGAGCAGGAACUCUAAUCCAAGGGUGGGGGAGAUCAGUUGGUUCCUUCACAGAAAAUAAGCCUGUUGUGUGGGCAUCUUGCUUGCCUGUAGAUCUUUGUUCCCAGUUCAGGAGGUUUUUAUUCAGUGCUUGCUUCAUUUACUGGAAAAGUUCACUGGGCCCACCUGUCAACUCCUUCCCCCACAGCUUCCAGCUCAGCAGCAAACUGUAGGGAACAGAUUUACUCCCCAGUUCCUACUGUAAAUAAUGCUUUAAGAACAGCAUUCCUUUUGGACAAUAUGUCAUAGACCCAAUUUUUAAUACUCCCAAGUCAGAUAUCUAACUAGAGAGUUUAGGAAAUGUUUGGUAUGAUCAAACUUUUCCCUUCAGUACACAAUUUAAUUUACGCAGAAGAGCAUCGGAGACAUUUGUCUCAUAGAUAUGAUUGACAUGAGUGAUAGGCUAAAACUAAAAUUUUAGUGGUUUGUGGAGUGGCUAGAAAACAUGAAUUGUAAGCAGUUUUUCAGAAUUUAAAAAUCUCUUAGUUUGAACAGUAGAAGAUGUAAAUAAGCAUAGAGACUGUUGGCAAGUUAUGUUUAUCACAAAACAAAGAAGAAGGCACAGAGGGUCCCUUUGACCCUUGAACUUGUGGUUACUAAUAGUAUUAAGGUUGGAAAUCAUGAGGAAGGACACAGAACAUAAACUGGGAUCUUGAAGACAGGCAUGUUGAUAAAAGUAGCCCUGAAGCCUUAAUAUUAGCAACAUCGAAGAUGGGAAAGACAGGAUUGAUUUAUUUGGGAACUAAGUUUACACAUUAUAUGUCUCAAUAUAAAACAAAAGCUAUGGCUUUAGAGUUUAACAGGUUAAAAAAAAAUAGGAGGAAAGGCAAAACAAAUGUAAGAAUAGUUUUUAAUCCAUUUUCUCACAAGCAGUGCACAGUGGGCCGGCAGGUACUUAAGUACCUUAUCCUAAUCCUGGAUGUGCUCAUACAGGCUGUCAAUUUGGGUCCGAAAGUAUUUGGAAAGCUCUCCUCGCUUUGCUUUCAAUGUUGGUGUCAAGAGCCCAUUUUCAAUGGAAAAUGGCUCUGGAUGAAGAAAAAUGGCUUUGACCUGGAAGAUGAACACACACACAUCCAUGCUCAUUAGUGAUUUGGACUUCUCUGCAGAGCCCCCUGAGUGCUCUGUGAAGAAAGUGAGGUUGAUGCAGUGAAAGGGUAAAGGUAACAGUAACACAUGCCCAUUCCCACAAACAUAAUUUAAGAAAGUAAUGAGUAGGGAGAAGGGAGAAUGGACAAUAAACAGCAAAAAAAGGGCGCUGUACAAGUAACUACAAAAGGUCAUUUUGUAGUUAAUGGCACAAAAUCUAAAAUCAAUUCCUUAGAAAUUAUACAUUUAAACCUCAUUAGAUGGAAACUUUAAACAAAACUUUCUGACAAGAGGCCAGUAUAACAUCAGUGGUAGCACACACCUGUUCAAAAGUUUUAAGGCCACUUUCUUUCCCAAUUUUCUGCAAGUCUUCUAAAAUGGCUUCCCUUACAACCUAAGAAUACAAAACAUCACUUAAAGCAUGGCUGUUUCAAAAAGCCUGAAGGGCUAAGCAUGAACCAACUCAAAGUGCCUGUCAAAGCCAUGCAGUAUGAAAGCAGGAAUAUAAAACUAUGCACAAGCACAUUAUAUGCCCAAUAUUGAAAGAAAAACUGAGAAGAAAAGGCACAUCUAAGUGUUAACAGUUUUCUCUGAAUAGCAUUUUUACUCUUCUUUCCCAAUCUUUUCCCACAAUGAACAUAUUAUUUUAAAUAGAAAAGAGAGUUUUAUUUUUUAAACUCUCCAUCCUAUCCCCGAGUCCCAUAAAACUAUUCAGUCUGUUUGGGCUGCAGCCACUUGUGACAGAUGCAGGAACUGGUGAGGCAUCCUCUCCUCCACGAUGGGCCCAUGGGUGUGCAUAAAGCUUUCCUAGGCAAGACUUACUUGGUUUUGGCACAGUUCCUCAAAGGAGCCCUUCACCCCAAGCUUGGCUGCAAAUGAGGGAAGUACAUCUGUGUCAGGAACCACCACUCCUACUAAGGAUGACUAUGGAAAGGAAAUAAAAGGUGCAAGGGCAUGAGAGAAGUUAUGUAGGGAUGUCCCCCAGUAGUUAAAUAAAGCAGAAUUAUGUCAUUGUAAUAGUUAUUUCCCCAAAACCUUAAAUCCAGUACUAGUGUUCUUUUCUCACCAUAUAUUUUCAACACCAUGGAACUGUAAUCCCAUUUUCCCACUCAAUAUCUCAUUACAAAGAUGUUCCAUUCAAAUCUGAUCCUUCAACAUUAAGCUUAAAGCGCCUCUGGCUUGUCCAUGUCAACUCUCCCCUUGUCCCCUAAAAGCUACAUUUAAGCACAGUGUGUAUAAAACAGUUCGUUGUUUUGGGAUAAGGAGUUCCUUAAAGCUACGUUUAAGCAUAGUAUGUAUAAAACAACAGUUUGUUGAUCAAACUUUUGUUUGUUGCUUUAUAUAUAUUGCAACAGUUUGUUGUUUUAUACAUACUGCUCUUAAACAUAGCUUUAAGGAACUCCUUAAGGAAUGGGAACUAAGUGCAAUGUGGAGCUCAUUUUUUACUGAAUCAUUACCUUUUAGUAUAGCCAUUCUAAACAAUUCUACUGACUUGUGUACAACGUCCAUCAUAGUUUUGAAAUUUUUUAAAUUGAAAUUGCCUUAUUUGAGGUUUGGAAUGUAACUUCAUUUUUUUUUUUUUUUUUAGUUUUAUAAGCUUGGAUCUUCUCAUUCUGAACCCAACUAUACAAAUUUCCUGUAGCUACAAGAACCAGCAUGGUUUGUGACUGAAAUGGGCUAUUGUUAAAAUGAUAUAUUACCCGUAAGCUCUCCCCGUGUACAAAAAUUUGUAACACUGGUUGACUCCUGUUGUAGAUAUUUUCUAUCUUCUCUGGUGCAAUGUAUUCUCCUUGGGCCAGCUUGAAAAUGUUCUUUUUACGGUCGAUGAUCUUCAGAGUUCCAUUCUACAUGAGACAGAUAAAAGUAUCAGUAUUUUUGAGCCACAGAGAUGAUAUCAGUGGGGAGAGUGGUGAAGUCACAGUCAUCUUUCUUCUCUAAAGCUGAUUUCUCCAGAGACUUUUGAGCUGUCUUUCAUUUCUCUUUCUUGGCUUUGGUGAAAGGGGAGGGAAGCAUCGUGCAGCAAGAACCUGUCUUUACUGUAUAUCUAUGUGGAGAGUCAAUGCGCAGCCUUAGAGAAAGUCUCCUGGAUCUACUGGAGUUAUGCAAAUUGAUGCCUCAUCCAAGGAAGAAAUUGCACAGCUCUCAAUUUCCAAUCACUAAUUUCCAAUUAGUUCAUUUUCAGAACUCUCAGAAAUAGAGGUGUUGUCUUUUGUUUAGACUUUUGAUUUGAUUUGAAUAGUUCUCCCACCACUUGACUCCCUGUUAUGUUUUCCUCCUUGUUAGAUCCGGGAGCAGGCUCAAACAGCUCCACUGUGCUAAUCAAGCAACUCAAUUACUGGGCUUGUUAGGACAGCAACAGGGCUGAGAGGACUCUGACCAGCCACCAAAGGUCAUUUGCAGCUUCAUUUCUCUGAACUAAUUGGUCUGAGGAGCUUAGGUCUUUAGGGAUUUGAAUUGUAGAAUUGGGACAAAUGGCAAAUAAAAUCCACAUGCUAACACCCUAAGUAGGGCGACUAACUAAACCAACACUGGAACUAUCACAAGGCCGACUUGAUAAAUUAGCCAUCAAUUCAGCCUAACGUUCAUUAUCUGAAAGUGAUUAAUAAGGUGCAGCCUUCUAUAACCCUGGUGUGGGGACAUAUCUGUUGCUUACAUCCUAGGCUUAUUAGAGUGUUAUUUAAUUCUGUUACUAGACAGAAACAAAUAUAUUAGCAAGAUACUACCAAACCCAAAUCAAUAAAAUGCAUCGUUAGGACCAGUGUUCUUAAAA